GUCUUGUCCUGCAAGGUGGAUUCCCAAUUCCAUUGUCCACAGCUGAAGCCCAUGCUAUUCUUGCCUCUCCAUUCUGGCCAUGUGGAUUCCUCCUCCAAUCAAGGACUUGCAAUUUGAAGAUACCAACUGAAAGUGUGUCAUCUUCCUUGAAGAGCAAGGUCAUCUUAAGUUUCUCAGAUAAUACUGAUGGAGAAUUGUACGGAAGUGACAAAGUUCAUUCUUCUAGGACUAACCAGUGUCCCAGAACUACAGAUCCCCCUCUUUAUCUUGUUCACCUUCAUCUACCUCCUCACUCUGUGUGGGAACCUGGGGAUGAUGUUGCUGAUCCUGAUGGACUCUUGUCUCCACACCCCCAUGUACUUUUUCCUCAGUAACCUGUCUCUGGUGGACUUUGGAUACUCCUCAGCUGUCACUCCCAAGGUCAUGGCUGGGUUCCUUAGAGGAGACAAGGUCAUCUCCUACAAUGCAUGUGCUGUUCAGAUGUUCUUCUUUGUAGCCUUGGCCACGGUGGAAAAUUACUUGUUGGCCUCAAUGGCCUAUGACCGCUAUGCAGCAGUGUGCAAACCCCUACACUACACCACCACCAUGACGGCCAGUGUAGGUGCCUGUCUGGCCCUAGGCUCAUAUGUCUGUGGCUUCCUAAAUGCCUCAUUCCACAUUGGGGGCAUAUUCAGUCUCUCUUUCUGUAAAUCCAAUCUGGUACAUCACUUUUUCUGUGAUGUUCCAGCAGUCAUGGCUCUGUCUUGCUCUGAUAAACACACUAGUGAGGUGAUUCUGGUUUUUAUGUCAAGCUUUAAUAUCUUUUUUGUUCUUCUAGUUAUCUUUAUCUCCUACUUGUUCAUAUUCAUCACCAUCUUGAAGAUGCAUUCAGCUAAGGGACACCAAAAAGCAUUGUCCACCUGUGCCUCUCACUUCACUGCAGUCUCCGUCUUCUAUGGGACAGUAAUCUUCAUCUACUUGCAGCCCAGCUCCAGCCACUCCAUGGACACAGACAAAAUGGCAUCUGUGUUCUAUGCUAUGAUCAUCCCCAUGCUGAACCCUGUGGUCUACAGCCUGAGGAACAGAGAAGUCCAGAAUGCAUUCAAGAAAGUGUUGAGAAGGCAAAAAUUUCUAUAAGUUUGGAAUUUUAACAUUGUUGUAUACACAAAAAUGUUGUUUCCCUCAUCUCAGACUUUCCUCAUGCAAUGAGUUACAUUUGAAACCCCACAAUACAUUUAAGUUCAUGAGGUGAUAUUCUUACCUCUUUAGAAGUCAAUUUUUUAAUAAAAAUAAAAUAUUAUCAGAAAUGUAAUACCUGAAUGAGGAAGGCUAAAUGGAAAUGUUAGAAUUUUUGGAACUUGCUGGUCAAAACUUACUAAUGACAUUCGGUUUACUCACUUGUUCCCCUUGCAUUUUUUCUACCACAUUCCAGUGCAAACAUACUUGUUAAACAGGGACACCAACAAGCCCACAAAAAAGUACAUGUUUAUGCCUCUUGUGGGCACAUAGGCAUUAGAAGGAGAAAUUUACUCAGAAGUAAAUGGAGUGUGGCUAGUUUUUAUAUAAAGGAUGUAAGUAAUUAAUUUAGUAUUAUAGUAUAAAUUUAUUUUUGAAUAGACUUUAAGAACAGUUUUAUGUUCACAGCAAAAUGGAGAGGUAAGUACAGAGAUUUCCCAUAUACCUUCUGCCCCCACAUACAUAUACCCUCCCUCAUUGUCAAUAUCCUCCAACAGAGUGCUACAUUUUUUACAAUUGAUGAACCUACAUUGACACAUCAUUAUCAUCUCAAGACCAUAAUUUACAUUAGGAUUCACUCUUGCUGUUGUCCCUUCUAUGGAUUUGAAUAAAUGUAUAAUGACAUCUAUUUAUCAUUAUAGUAUCAUAUUGAGUAGUUUCACUGCUCUAAAGCUCUUCUAUGCUCUACUUACUCAUUCUUCCUUCUUCCCUAACCCCUGACAACUACUGAUCUUUUUCUGUCUCCACAGUUUUGCUUUCUCCAGAAUGUCAUAUAGUUAAAAUCAUAUGGUAUGUAACCUUUCCAUAUUGGCUUAUUUCACAUAGUAAUAUGCAUCUGUUUUCUCCAUAACUUUUCGUGGCUUGAUAGCUCAUUUCAUUUUAGCACUGAAUAUUGUCUAUUGUCAAGUGGUAUCACACUUUAUUCAUGUACCUACUGAAGGAUAUUUUGGUUGCUUCCCUAGUGUUGGCAGUUAUGAAUAAAGCCGCUAUAAACA